GUAGUCGCGAUCCUGAGGUAACGGGUGAGUAUCCCGCGCGGGGAUCGCUUGUCCCCUUGGGGCCUUGUCAGUCGGUGGGUGGGCUUCGUUUGACAGUUGCGUGACCAGCCCCUCGGCCUCGCUUCUAUCCUUGCCUUGUGUGUUUAUGACGAACCCUCCGGGCUUGCGGGCCCAGACGUGAGAGAGCUUUCCGCUGAAGAUGACGGGCCUGCUUUCCAGGGCGGCUUGUCGAAAGCCCGGGAGCAUCUGGCCGCUUCCGCCUCAACCAUGGGCUGGGGUUUUGUGAGCUACUAGUGCCAAGGGUUUUCUUUCCACCAGACCACCGCUAUAAGUUUAUACCAUGGAUAGCACAAAGGAGAAGUGUGACAGUUACAAAGAUGAUCUUCUGCUUAGGAUGGGACUUAAUGAUAAUAAAGCAGGAAUGGAAGGAUUAGAUAAAGAGAAAAUUAACAAAAUUAUAAUGGAAGCCACGAAGGGGUCCAGAUUUUAUGGAAAUGAGCUCAAGAAAGAAAAGCAAGUCAACCAACGAAUUGAAAAUAUGAUGCAACAAAAAGCUCAAAUCACCAGCCAACAGCUAAGAAAAGCACAAUUACAGGUUGACAGAUUUGCAAUGGAAUUAGAACAAAGCCGAAAUUUGAGCAAUACCAUAGUGCACAUUGACAUGGAUGCUUUCUAUGCAGCUGUAGAAAUGAGGGACAAUCCAGAAUUGAAGGAUAAACCCAUUGCUGUAGGAUCAAUGAGUAUGCUGUCUACUUCAAAUUACCAUGCAAGGAGAUUUGGUGUUCGUGCAGCCAUGCCAGGAUUUAUUGCUAAGAGGCUGUGCCCACAACUUAUAAUAGUGCCCCCCAACUUUGACAAAUACCGAGCUGUGAGUAAAGAGGUUAAGGAAAUACUUGCUGAUUAUGAUCCCAAUUUUAUGGCCAUGAGUCUUGAUGAAGCCUACUUGAAUAUAACAAAGCACUUAGAAGAAAGACAAAAUUGGCCUGAGGAUAAAAGAAGGUAUUUCAUCAAAAUGGGAAGCUCUGUAGAAAAUGACCUUCAGAAUUUGUAUAUUCAAAGAAGCAUAACUUUCACAGAUAAUCCAGGAAAGGAAGUUAAUAAACUGAGUGAGCAUGAACGAUCCAUCUCUCCACUACUUUUUGAAGAGAGUCCUUCUGAUGUGCAGCCCCCAGGAGAUCCUUUCCAAGUGAACUUUGAAGAACAAAACAAUCCUCAAAUACUCCAAAACUCAGUUGUUUUUGGAACAUCAGCCCAGGAAGUGGUAAAGGAAAUUCGUUUCAGAAUUGAGCAGAAAACAACACUGACAGCCAGUGCAGGCAUUGCCCCAAAUACAAUGUUAGCAAAAGUAUGCAGUGAUAAGAAUAAACCAAAUGGACAAUACCAAAUUCUUCCCAAUAGACAAGCUGUGAUGGACUUCAUCAAGGAUUUACCCAUUAGAAAGGUUUCUGGAAUAGGAAAAGUUACAGAGAAAAUGUUAAAGGCCCUUGGAAUUAUUACAUGUACAGAACUUUACCAACAGAGGGCAUUGCUUUCUCUCCUUUUCUCUGAAACAUCUUGGCAUUAUUUCCUUCAUAUCUCCUUGGGUCUAGGUUCAACACACCUGACGAGGGAUGGAGAGAGGAAAAGUAUGAGCGUUGAGAGGACAUUCAGUGAGAUAAAUAAAGCGGAAGAGCAAUACAGCCUAUGUCAAGAACUUUGCAGUGAGCUUGCUCAGGAUCUACAGAAAGAAAGACUUAAGGGUAGAACUGUUACCAUUAAGUUGAAGAAUGUGAAUUUUGAAGUAAAAACUCGUGCAUCUACAGUUUCAUCUGUUGUUUCUACUGCAGAAGAAAUAUUUGCCAUUGCUAAGGAAUUGCUAAAAACAGAAAUUGAUGCUGAUUUUCCACAUCCCUUGAGAUUAAGGCUUAUGGGUGUUCGGAUAUCUAGUUUUCCCAAUGAAGAGGACAGGAAACACCAACAAAGGAGCAUUAUUGGCUUUUUACAGGCUGGAAACCAAGCCCUGUCAGCCACUGAGUGUACAUUAGAGAAAACUGACAAAGAUAAGUUUGUAAAACCUCUAGAAAUGUCUCAUAAGAAGAGUUUCUUUGAUAAAAAACGAUCAGAAAGGAAAUGGAGUCACCAAGAUACAUUUAAAUGUGAAGCCGUGAAUAAACAAAGUUUCCAGACAUCACAACCAUUCCAAGUUUUAAAGAAGAAGAUGAAUGAGAAUUUGGAAAUAUCAGAGAAUUCAGAUGACUGUCAGAUACUUACCUGUCCUGUUUGCUUUAGGGCUCAAGGGUGCAUCAGUCUGGAAGCCUUGAAUAAACAUGUAGAUGAAUGUCUUGAUGGACCUUCAAUCAGUGAAAACUUUAAAAUGUUCUCGUGUUCACAUGUUUCUGCUACCAAAGUUAACAAGAAAGAAAAUGUUCCUGCUUCUUCACUUUGUGAGAAGCAAGAUUAUGAAGCCCAUCCAAAAAUUAAAGAAAUAUCUUCAGUAGAUUGUAUAGCUUUAGUAGAUACUAUAGAUAACUCAUCUAAAGCAGAAAGCAUAGAUGCUUUAAGUAAUAAGCAUAGCAAGGAAGAAUGUUCUAGUCUCCCAAGCAAGUCUUUUAAUAUUGAACACUGUCAUCAGAAUUCUUCUUCUACUGUUUCAUUGGAAAACGAAGAUGUUGGAUCAUUUAGACAAGAAUACCGCCAGCCUUACUUAUGUGAAGUGAAAACAGGCCAAGCUCUAGUUUGUCCUGUUUGUAACGUAGAACAAAAGACUUCAGAUCUAACCCUGUUCAAUGUGCAUGUGGAUGUUUGCUUAAAUAAAAGUUUUAUCCAAGAAUUAAGAAAGGAUAAAUUUAACCCAGUUAAUCAACCCAAAGAAAGCUCCAGAAGUACUGGUAGCUCAAGUGGAGUACAGAAGGCUGUAACAAGAACAAAAAGGCCAGGAUUGAUGACAAAGUACUCAACAUCAAAGAAAAUAAAACCAAACAAUCCCAAACAUACCCUUGAUAUAUUUUUUAAGUAAACAUUGAACAUUUUAUCAUUAAUUUUUAAUUGAAACUAGUUAUUUUAUAAUCAAUGAAUUUGUUCUUUCUGAUUUUAAGUUUGCAGAUUUAUUUAGUGAAGGCAAGUGCAAUAAUCCUUCCUCAGAUGAUGUUUGCUUUUCUAAGAUACAUAUACUGAUUCUGUGUAUCUUUUUUAUAACCAUGAGAAUUUUACUUCCAUUAUACAUCAAUUGGAAAUCAAUCCUGUUAAGAGAUAAUUCUUAAAAGGGAAAUUAGGAAUGGGAUAAGAAGGUGAUUUUUUUAUUAUUUUUAUACUGAAUAUAAAAACAUUUGUAAGGGCUCUCAAAGAUUCACACAUGCCUAUAUUAUCAUAAGAAUUUUUCAGCACUUAACUACUUUGUUGGCAUUGAUCCUAGUGUCUUUAAAUACUUCAUGAGCAUUCAUAAUUAAAAUUUAUCUUAAGUUCUAUGAAGAGUAUUAAUGUAACUAGCAUAAGUGGUUUUCUUCAGGAAAAUAAAUAUCACAGUAUUAUCUGUGUUAAAAUGGUUUUUGCCUAAAAUAUAAUUUUUAAUUUGGCUUUUCUUAUUUAAAAUUCCAUUAUCUUAUGAAUAAGCACUUGAAUCAGUUUUUAAAAUAUUUAGUCUAAGAUGAUUCAAAGUAGUUUUAUUUUAAUACAGGACUUUUAAAUGGCAGUAUUUCAUUUCUUGUCAAUUAUGUUGGUACUUUCCACAAAUCUAUAAAGAAGGAUAAAUUGUACCAUCAUUUUAUUAUAAUCCUCAAGAGAAAAUGUGUAAUUCAAAAGAUUAAUGUGUAUUAAAACACAUUAUGUAUCUUAGUUACAUUUCUAUCAGUACUUUUAUUAAUAUUUGUGAAAGAAGACAGCUUAAUAGUAGUUAGCUUAAGUAGUUUCUCCAAGUACUUUUGUGCUAUCAAUGAGUUCUUCUCAAAAAAUAAUUAGUUAGGCCAGGCACAAUGGCUCACACCUGUAAUGCCAGCCCUUUGGGAGGCCGAAUGGGCAGAUCACUUGAGGUCAGGAGUUUGAGACCAGCCUCGCCAACAUGGUGAGACCCUGUCUCUACUAAAACGAUAAAAAAAAAAAAAAAAUUAGCCAGGCUUGGUGGCACACGCCUGUAAUCCCAGCUACUCAGAUGGCUGAGGCAGGAGAACUACUUGAACCUGGGAGGUCAAAGCUGCAGUCAGCCAAGAUCUUGCCACUGUACUCCAGCCUGAAGAGCGAGACUCUGUCUCAAUAAUAUAAUAAUAGUUAUUAUUUAAUUGCAACAUGAAGUUGGAAGCCAUUUUCUGUUACUUCUUUAAGGAGCUAAAUCUUUUAUAUUUUUGUUUUCUCUCCCCUUGCGUUUCAUAUUUUAGCUUAUGAUCUAAAUAUAUAUUUUGUAUAUUAUAAUAUUUUAGGAAUAGCUUAAUUAAGAACUCACAGACUUUGACAAAGUGGUAACUAGACUUUUAAUUACUAGAUUCUUCAAAUUAGGCUUAAUGCCUGCUAGCAUGCCAAUCCAAUCCCAUGACUGAUGUUAUUAUACACUAUGGCAAAUACAAAGUUGUAGUAUUAUGGUUCUUGAUGGUGUGAUUUACUUAUGUAAAUUAUGUACAAAUUUAAGUUCAAUGAAACACUGAUUUAAUGUACUGAAAGGUAAAUAGUACCAUAGUGAAUUAUUUUCUGUCUUGCCUUAGGUUUAUUUUUAUUAUCUUCAAUAUUAGAAUAAAUGCUAAAUUAUUUUCAUUUAAGGAUUUAUGUAGUUGAAUAUUAUCAUUUAGUAAUAUUUAAUCAUUUGAAAUAAAAUUUAAAGCUUUAAUUGAUCUAAUAGAGAUGGUUUUCUACUUUUCCACUCUUCCUCCCUCUUAUGCCUUCACUUUUGUUUUCUGUGCCCAGAAUUUUCUUCACAUUCUUUACUACCUGUUUUGUCUAUUAUAUCCAACCCAUUUUCUUUUUAUUAUAAUUUUGAUUUGGGGCAUUUGAAGAAAAUACAGCAAAACUACAAGAACUGGUAAUAAGCAUGCAUAAUCUCACCUACUUAGUGAACCUAAUAUAAACCUAAUAUAAAGAACCACCGUAUUUGCAAUAUAUAUAACUGGUGAAAAACUAGUGUCCAGAAUAUAUAAAUGAUCCCUAUGAAUCAGUAAGAAAAAGACAGUCAAUAGAAAUUUGGACAAAAGACUUUAUAUGGCAUUUCAAGUGAAAGGAAAUCCAGAUGACCAAGAAACAUGAAAAUAUUCCCAGCCAUAUUAAUAUUUGAGAAGUAAAAAAUAAAACUACAAGGAGGUAUUACAUCUUUACCUUAUUUGCAAAAAUGAAAUGAUCUAAUGAUACUAAGUUUUGGUGAUGAUGUCAGCUCUUACAUUGAAAACAAUCACUGUGGAAAAAUUUGUCCCUCAGUAAAUUUAAAGAUAAACAUGCUCAAAACCUAGCAAUUGCACUCUGAAGUAUACAUCUUUGCAGGUUAUCUUUCAUUACAGUUAUUUUUUUCCCUGUCAGGACCCUAACUAAUACAAUGCCUUGGGAAAACUAAUGAACAUGUAUCCUAGGAAGCAUGUACAAGAAAGUUCUUCCCAGUCAGGAAGGUGGCCAAGAAAAAAAUUUUUUAAUGUUCAUAGCAGCACUGCAAUAUCCAAAAGUUAGAAAUGAACCAAAUAUUCAGCAAUGGUAGAAUGGUUAAAUUGUACCAUGGCAUUUAUAUUGAAACAGUAGAAUUCUACACAGUGGUGAAAAUGAAGGAAAUAGCUAACCACAACAUAGAUGAAUAUCACAGACAUAGCAUAGAGCAAAAGAAGCAAAUCACAGAAGGAUGCCAUCAACAUGAUUCCAUUUGUAUAAAGUUUAAAACAGUAUAAACUGAACAACUAUAUUGUUUUAAGGGUAUAUAGUUAUAUAUAUGAGAUACAACUGUAAAGAAAAGCAAGUGUUUUGCUGUCCCCAGAACCAGAAUAAUGAUUUCCUCUGUGGAGAAGUACAGCAGUGUGAUUGGGGAGUGGCACCUGGUGCUUCUGGGAUGCUGGCAAUGUUCUAUUUCUUGUCUUGGGUGGUGAUUGCAUGGAUGUUCACUUUUAAAAUACUCUUUAUACAUAUAUAUUUUAUAUAUUCUUGUUCAUAUAUAACCUUUAUAAUAAAGAGAAAAAAAUGGCAAAAACUGCUUUCGUUAACAAGAUGAUAUUUUCCUCCAACUCUGCAGGCUAGCUAAUUUCAAUCGAGAAAAAAAUACAUUUUUUUCUUCUAGAACCUUGCUGAACACAGCAAGAAAGAGCCAUCCCAUGCAAAAUUUUUAGUUUUUCUCCUAGCAUUUCCCCUAAGGCUACAGCCUCAAUCAGUAUUUGGUCUUCUUUCCAAAGACAGCUGUUGACAGUUAGACCAAAUAUUUUUUUGCCGUUUGUGAUGGUUAAUAUUGAGUGUCAACUUGAUUGGAUUAAAUGAUGCAAAAUAUUGUUCCUGGGUGUGUCUGUGAGGGUAUUGCCAAAGAAGAUUAACAUUUGAGUCAGUGGGCUCAAGAAGCAGAUCCACCCUCAAUCUGGUUGUGCACCAUCUAAUCAACUGCCAGCAUAGCUAGGAUAAAAGCAGGCAGAGGAAGGUGGAAGGACUACACUGGCUAAGUCUUCUGGCCUCCGUCUUUCUCCUGUGCUGCAUGUCUUCUGCCCUUGAACAUCAGACUCCAAGUUCUUCAGCUUUUGGACUCUUGGACUUCCACCAGUGAUUUGCCAGGGACUAUCAGGCCUUCAGCCACAGACUGAAGGGCUGCACCAUCUGCUUGUCUGCUUUUGAGGUUUUGGGACUCAGACUGGCUUCCUGGCUUCUCAGCUUGCAGACUGUGGGACUUCACCUUGUGAUUGUGUGAGUCAAUUUUCCUAAGAAACUCCCCUUCAUAUAUACAUCUAUUAGUUCUGUCCCUCUAGAGGACCCUAAUACACCACCAAACAAGUCACCAGUUUUCCAGUCUGUGGUAUUUGUGUCCCCACUCCCUAAAUUCUUCUCUCCAACCCUAAGUCAAUUUGUUAUAUUAGGCUUUGUUAUUUGCAGUACCCUAUUUCUGUAUCAGUUCAGUCACAAGCUUCCUGGUGCCUCUUCCUUGUUGAGUCACAUGGGGACAUGCUUAAUUCUCCCAGAAAUGUGUGACAGCAUGUGCAAAAUAUUGCCAACCAAGGAAGCUCAACCAAUCCUUGGUGUCCAAGGUGUUUACUGGAAGUCAGUCACAUAGGCAUGCAUCACCCAUGUGACUGACCUUACCCGUUGAGUCUCAAGACCCCAGGGGUGUAGUGAUACCUCAUGGCCCAGGGCUUCAGCCAUUCAAAAACAGACAUUCGCCAUGAUUCAUACUGUUAGCAUAAACUAUCUCGUCAAACUAACAAAAUGCAGCCCAAGGCCUCAGGCAUACUAGAACACUAUUAUCAAACUGGAAAUUCCACGAGCUCAGGUCAUUUCCCAGGAGCUAGUCAAGGAAGGGCCAGUACGUGAAGACACCUCUCUUUGAAAAGUGCAGGGCUGGAGUAACCUGAGGCUGCUAGGUUAACCCUUUACUGCAUUAAUGUCAAAUUAUUAGAAUUGUAUUCAAAUAAAAUAUAAAAAAGAAAGAUCACUUAGAGUAACUUUUUCCUGCCUCACUUGAAUAAUGCAGAGACACUUCAAAUUCGUAACAUGUUUAGGGGGUCUCAAGGAGGAUGGGCUAUGCGUUUUGAAUAUAUGCAUAUAAAACAACAAAUGACAUAGGCCUAAUAAUUUCUUUGCAUGUGUAUAAUCCUCUCUUCAAUGUAAUUCAAAGGUCUCUUUUUUAAUAUCAGUCUUUACAUUGUCCCUGUAAUAUAGAGCUAUACACCUUUCCUCAAUCUUUUGUGAUAGUAGGAAAAGUAGCAUUAUAAGAAGUAUUUAUAAAUUUAAUUCACUCCACCAGAAAUGUUUUAUUUUAAAGUUAGCAUGGGACUUGUGGUAUCCGCAAGGUCAGUGUCCCCACUGAAGAAGUGGCCUUCUAGAGUAAGAAGUUUCAGCAUCAACAUGGGUAAUGGAAGCCAUAUAACAGAACUUAAGAAGGAACUUUGUGCUAAGAAAAUGUAGACAGUGGUUAUAGGCAUAUAUGUAAGAAGGCUGUAAGUUAAAGGCAAGAGAGAUGUAGCAAUUAAUAGGAGAUAUUUUUUCUGCCAUCAUUAACAAAUGUAUUUGUUUACUACUCCUUACUUUUUAACUCAUCCACCUUGUAUCCACUGCUACCUCUGCCAACCCUGUAUCUGUUACUGAAUUCUGUCUACUCUUGUAGGGCCUCUUGAAAAUGAAAAUAUCCAUUUGUUUCCAUCUCUUUUGUCAAGCCCUUAUCAGUUGUCUAAACUCUUGACUUUCCAACUGAUUUGUCAGUUUUCCCUGCUCUAAACCAUCUUAUGCAUUUUUUACAGAUUAGCUAUAAACAGCAUUCCCAUAAUAGCACUCUCAUGUCAAAAAAAAAAAAAAAGCAGUUUUCAAAAGCUCUCAACUGUCUCCAAGAUUUAGCAGUGGAAUGAGUAGGAAAAGGGAGUGAUUUUUAGUGUAUGAUUAUUUAUGUGGUGUAAAUGCUCCCACCAUGACAGAUUUCAAGUUAUGUGAUGUCAGCCAGUUCACAAAAUUCCUGAAACUUUAACAGCUCUUGCAAGCCAAUACAAGCUAGCUCCUAUAUAUCACUGUCCAUGAUGCACUCUAAACACUGGCUUGGCAUUCAGGGUUUCCUGAACAGACCAAGCUGUUUCUCCUUUCUGGCAUCUGUGCUCCAUUGUUCCCUCUGCCCAGAAUAUGCUUCCUGAAUGCCCCUUUUCUCUCUCCCACCUACAUAAUUACUCAUCUUUCAACUCAGCUCAAGGGCCACCUUCAGAAAAGUGUUCCUUGCCCUCUGGAAAAAUUGAUCAGUCACUAUUUUUUGCUCCUGUUUCCCUACAAAGACCCUGAAACAUUCUUUGCAUGGCCCCCGAUGUUGGUUUCUCCCUACCAGAUUGUAGGCCCCAAGAGAUCCUGGGCUAUCUUUCACUUAUCUCUGAAUUCCAAGUAUGAAGUGUAUGGCCUGGCACACAGUAGAUACGGAGAGUCAUUUGUUGACAUGUAAAUGAAUAAAUAGUAUGUGUCCAAAAGUGUUUACUACUAUCUUAUUGUUUUUAUCUGGGAAGACAGAAUGGUGGCUAAGGGCUGCUGUCACACUGGGUCCUAAAGAGUGGACAUUCCAGAAAGAGACAAUUGCAUUUAUUUCCCUUUAUUAGAUAAUGGCUUGCUUUAUACAUGUUUUAUUAUUAUACUGUGUCGUUUUGGAGUGGCUUGGGAGUAUUUGGAAGAAGGCUUAAAAUAUGACUAUUAACCUGGGGCUAAAAAAAACUGUUUUUGAGGAAAUAUUUCAUUUAAAAAAAUCAUACCUGGUGUACCUGGUGCUGAACUGUUGUUUUUAGAGACAAGGUCUCACCGUCACCCAGGCUGAAAUACAUUGUCAUGAUCAUAACUCACUGCAGCCUGGAACUCUUGGGAUCAAGAUCCUCUCAUCGCAGCUUCCCAAGUAGCUGGGACUACAGGCUGGUGCCAUGAUGCCCAGCUAAGUUUUUGUAUUUUUUUGUUGAGAUAGGAUCUUGCUAUGUGGCCUAGAUUGGUCUUGAACUCCUGGCUUCAAGCAUUCCUCCUUCCUCAGUCUCCCAAAGCUCUGGGAUUAACAGGCAUCAGCCACCAUGCCUGGCCCUGGUACUGAAUUUUCUUUGAAGUAAGGUUCCAUUUUGAAAAGCAGUGAUAUAUUUGAACACACUUUGUGUUGGUAGGAUUUUAGUAAACCUCACAGAGAGGUGAUGCUUAUUUCCCUGGAGAAAAAACUGUUCUUUAAUUGUAUAAUUAAGGACUAAUCGCUUUUGCUUUGUAAUACAUAACUGAAUUAAGUUGUUCAAGAAAAACUCAAAUGACAUCAUGGUGACUAUUGGCAACAUGAUUCCAUUUAUUAAGCAAACCAUAAUAUUGAACUGUUCCCCUUACCAGUACGAGGUAAUUGUGAUAGUCUUACUUUGUAACUGCUGCUGUCUACAGAAUGCUCAGGGAGAUUAAAGAUAAUUCAGAGGCAAAUGGUACUAACCCUUCUAACCUCAGCCUGUAAAGUGUAGUAUGAUUUCAAACUCUUUCCUGUAUACACAUACACACACACACACACACACACACACACACACACACACACUACCUCUGCCAACCACAUACCUAUCAUUGAGUUCUGUCUACUCUUGUAGGGCCUCUUGAAAACACUUCUUUCCAUUUCUUUUAUCAGGUUCUUAUCAGUUGUCUAAUAUCUGGCCUUCUAACUCAUUGCUUAGCUUUCACCAGUUUCUUUCCCUGCUUUAGAUCAUCUUGUGCAUUUUUGUAGACAAUACUUUCCUAAUAUCACUCAUGGUCUUGGGUGUCUAUGGAGAGAGUGAGAGAGAGAGAGAUUCCCUAAAUUGGAGACAAAAAGGAAAAAAAAGUUGGGUCACUUCUAGGAUCAAAUCUAGUUCUCUUUUAUGAAGGCUCAAAAGUUUUUUCCCUCUCAGAAUAUGCUAAACUUCAAAUGUGAUCUCUGAAACCAUCCGCAAGUCUGAGAUACGCCAUGGUUUUUUGGGUUUUGCUAGCAAUUCUGGGCAGAGAUCCUGGUUGUCCUUCAACAUUCUACUUUUCUGCCAUAUUAUUAGAAUUUUAGCUUGGCACAUGAUCACCCAGAAUAGACUAAUGUAUUUCAUCAAUUCUUUAUAAACCACUAAGAAAUAAUACCUAAGAUAGGGAGUCUAACAGGUUACCACUGCAUAAAUAUGGGACACCAAGGUUUAUACCUUCAGAGCAAGGAUAAAGGAGAAAUCUUCCAUGAAGAAAGAGGGAGCAAAGUGUAGGGGUGGGUUGCCCCUACACACCUGUGGGUGUUUCUCGUAAGGUGGGACGAGAGAUUUGGAAAAGAAAAAGACACAGAGACAAAGUAUAGAGAAAGAAAUAAGGGGAACCGGGGAACCAGCGUUCAGCAUAUGGAGGAUCCCGCCAGCCUCUGAGUUCCCUUAGUAUUUAUUGAUCAUCUGUGGGUGUUUCUCAAAGAGGGGGAUGUGUCAGGGUCACAAGACAAUUGUGGGGAGAGGGUCAGCAGACAAACACGUGAACAAAGGUCUUGGCAUCAUAGACAAUGUAAAGGAUUAAGUGCUGUGCUUUUAGAUAUGCAUACACAUAAACAUCUCAGUGCUUUACAAAGCAGUAUUGCUGCCCGCAGGUCCCACCUCCAGCCCUAAGGCGGUUUUUCCCUAUCUCAGUAGAUGGAGCAUACAAUCGGGUUUUAUACCGAGACAUUCCAUUGCCCAGGGACAGGCAGGAGACAGAUGCCUUCCUCUUGUCUCAACUGCAAGAGGCAUUCCUUCCUCUUUUACUAAUCCUCCUCAGCACAGACCCUUUACGGGUGUCGGGCUGGGGGACGGUCAGGUCUUUCCCUUCCCACGAGGCCAUAUUUCAGACUAUCACAUGGGGAGAAACCUUGGACAAUACCUGGCUUUCCUAGGCAGAGGUCCCUGCGGCCUUCCGCAGUUUUUGUGUCCCUGGGUACUUGAGAUUAGGGAGUGGUGAUGACUCUUAAGGAGCAUGCUGCCUUCAAGCAUCUGUUUAACAAAGCACAUCCUGCACCGCCCUUAAUCCAUUCAACUCUGAGUUGACACAGCACAUGUUUCAGAGAGCACGGGGUUGGGGGUAAGGUCACAGAAUCUCAAGGCAGAAGAAUUUUUCUUAGUACAUAACAAAAUGGAGUCUCCUAUGUCUACUUCUUUCUACACAGACACAGUAACAAUCUGAUCUCUCUUGCUUUUCCCCACAGCAAAGCAAUUUGCAUGCUCAGCCUUGGCACUGGUUGGAAGGAGGGACUGCCAGUGAGAAUUUGAACCAUAAACCAGUACACAUGUAGGCUUGUAAUCUGAAUUCACACAAAUGGUAUCAUCCUAAAGAGCUCAAGCAGAAAAUGUAAUUAAAGUGAGGUUAGUAUUGCCCCUAGUGACUGGCAGAAGCAUAUGCAAAUCCUCUAUGGAAGAACUCAACUUCAAUUCAGGCAGACAACUUAGUAUCUCAAUUAAAAAGAUGUGAUAAUGUGAAAAAUAGGUGUUACAGAAUUGAUGACUACAAUGUAUCUCCCAUCCUUGAAGCUCACACCCUCCCAGCUAGGGGUAGCCAUGUGACUGAGUUUUGACUAAUGGGAUAUAAAAGGAAGUACUGGCCGGGUGCGGUGUCUCACGCCUGUAAUCUCAGCACUUUGGGAGGCCAAGGCGGGUGGAUCACCUGAGGUCAGGAGUUCGAGACCAGCCUGGCCAAGAUGGUGAAACCCCGUCUCUACUCAAAAUACAAAAAAGUAGCUGGGCGUGGUGGCACACACUUGUGAUCCCAGCUACUCAGGAGGCUGAGGCAAGAGAAUCGCUUGAACCCGGGAGACGGAGGUUGCAGUGAGCUGAGAUUGCACCACUGCACUCCAACCUGGGUGACAAAGCGAGACCUUGUCUCAAAAAAAAAAAAAAAAAAAGGAAGUACUGUGUGUGGUUGCUUCUGGGAACCUUCCUUUCUUGCAGCUGUAGCAUUCUGUUUGCCUCUUCUUUCUAUUUCUCUGUUCCAUCCUGCUGCCUGGAAGCAGAUGCUGCCGUUUACACCUGAACAUAAGGGUUGCACAGGGGGAUGGUAGAGUAGUGGGCUGCAGGGGCUGAUUCUUGGGGCUUUGUAAAACAGAGACAUAUCAGCACUGGCCUGCACACUUUGAGACUUUCACAAGAAACAAAUUAAAAAAUUGUUUAAGCCAUAGUUACUUGGGUUUUCCUAUUAAUUAUAGCUGAAUCCUAGCUGAUAAAGGACAUAAAGAUUAUUAAGACAUGUUUGUCCUCAAAAAAUGGAGAGCCACCCCAGGGACAGUUUCUAUUCAAUGUAGGGAGGGCUAUAAUAGAUGAAUAUACAAAGUGGGAGUCUAGGGAGAAAUCGUCUGGUAGAGGAGGGCAAAGAGAAAUCUAGGAAGAUGUUUUUAAAAAUAUGGAAUCCUUGAACAGGACCUGGUUUUAAAGGUUUACUUCAGAAUUGAACAUAUUUUUUUAGUCUAGACCUUUAGGGGAAAAACUUAAAGCUUUCAGGACUCAAAGACAAGUUACUGUUCCCAUGGCUAAAUUGCAUUCCAUAUUUAUUUGACAAAUACUUAUUGCAGGUCGGGUACUGUUUUAGCCACUGGAGAUGCAGUAAGAAACUUAAUUAAUUUUUUUUUUUUUUGAGACAGAGUCUUGCUCUGUCACCCAGGUUGGAAUGCAGUGACAUGAUAACAGCUUGCUGCAGCCUUGACCUCCGUGGCUCAGGCCAUACUCCCAUCUCAGCUUCCCAAGUAGCUAAGACUACAGGUCUGCCCCACCACCACCAGCUAAUUUUUAAAUUUUUUGUGGAGACUGGAGUCUCACUAAGUUGCCCAGGUUGGCCUCAAACUCCUGGCCUCAAGCCAUCCUCCCACUUCGGCCUCUCAAAUUGCUGGGAUUAUAGGCAUGAGACACCACGCCUGGCCCAACAAAGUUUUAAAAAUCACUGUAUUUAUGAAGUUUACAUUCUAGUUGUGGAAACCGACACUAAACAAAUAGACAUUUCAGUGGUAAGUGUUACAAAGGAAAGAGACAACAGCAUAAGGGAAUGGAACAUGAAGGUAGGGGACACUUUUAGAAUAAGAUGAUCCGAGAAGGCUCCUCUGAGGAAGUGACAUUUAACCUGAAACCUUAAUGAUACGAAGGAUCAAAACUAUUUUAAAAAUUCGGAAGUGGAGGUGGGGGAGAGAAGUUCUAGGCAAAGGGAGGAAAUAGAAGCUGAUGGCUCUCCACCAGGAAACAGUGGAUGAAGAAUGGAGAAGAAUUGUAGGGCCCAAGAUCAGAGAGAUGAGUAGGGCCAGAUCAUGUGGGCAAGCUUUUAUGUAUUAGCACGCUUAGAAUUAAUAUUCUGCUUGAGAACUAACCUGAUAUUUGAAACAGAGUGAAAAAGAAAAUACCUCCCACAGUAUACUUCAUAGCUUCUUAUUUAGCCCAAGCUGUCAGGGAAAUAAAGUCCAGCUAUGGCUAAGUUUCACAUAAUGCACUGCUUUGGAGUUUUUGUCUCAUCUGUUAGAGUAAGAUAAGUACCACAUACUAUUAUAAGGCUAUAUAGCAUAAAAUGAUGAUGCAUUUUCUCCUGUCAUUGAUAAGAGGAUUUUUUUAAAAGUAAAUUUCUUGGUUUAGAAUUUGAAAGCAGUUUCAAACUUGGAUAACACAAUUCAGAUCUUUUUUUAAAAUUAUUUUUUAUUUAUAUUAAAAAAAAAUUUUUUUUUUGAGAUAGGGUCUGGCUCUAUCACGCAGACUGGCACACAGUGGCACAAUCUUGGCUCAUUGCAACCUCUGCCUCCCAGGCUGAAGCCAUCCUCCCACCUCAGCCUCCCAAGUAGCUGGGACUACAGGCAUGCACCACCAUGCCUGGCUAAUUUUUGUAGAGAGGGGGUCUCACUUUGUUACCCAGACUGGGAGAUUUUUCUGUACUUGGCUGUAUGCUUUCCAUUGAUCUGCUGCUGUUUUCACUAUUAUUCCUUCUUUUGUGUGGGUAUUUUCUUUUGAUUUUUAGAAUUUUACUUGUAAACAUGCUACAUAUACAUAUAAUUUGGUGCCCUGUUUUUCCAUUUACAUAUUAUACUUUCCAUAUUAGUACAUUGUCUGAUAUUUCUGCAUAAUACUCAAUUCAACUUACCUGCUAUUGUUUUUAUCAUAUCUCUAUUACAAACAUUAGGCCCAUUUCCCUUUUUUAAAAGAGGAAAGUUUGAGGUUAUGGGCGGUGUUCUGAUAAAAUAAAUAAUAUUUUGUCAUGUUUGUUUUUUCAUUGAUUAGGAAACAUUGUUUUGAAUUUAAUGCCUCAAAUUUGGUGCACAAUAAUUUGAAGGGAAAAACUGACAAGUUUGAAAUGAACAUUGAUAUUACAUAAUUUACAUUAAAAUGAUACAUCUUUUGUAAAUUUGUAAGAAGAAUAAAUAAAUGAAAACCUGAUUACCUUU